AGCAAUGGAGAAUGUCACUACAAUGAAUGAGUUUCUUCUACUUGGCCUGACUGGUGUUCAGGAGCUGCAGCCUUUCUUCUUUGGGAUUUUCUUAAUCAUUUACCUGAUAAACUUGAUUGGAAAUGGAUCUAUAUUGGUGAUGGUUGUUUUGGAACCACAACUCCACUCCCCUAUGUAUUUUUUUCUGGGAAACCUUUCUUGUCUGGAUAUUUCUUAUUCUUCAGUGACACUGCCCAAGCUGCUCGUAAACCUCGUGUGCAGUCGCAGGGCUAUAUCUUUUCUAGGCUGUAUCACCCAGCUACACUUCUUCCACUUUUUGGGAAGCACAGAGGCCAUUUUACUGGCUAUCAUGGCCUUUGACCGUUUUGUUGCCAUCUGCAAUCCUCUUCGCUACACUGUCAUCAUGAACCCCCAGGUGUGUAUUCUGUUGGCAGCUGCGGCCUGGCUCAUCAGCUUCUUUUACGCUCUGAUGCAUUCUGUCAUGACUGCACACCUGAGUUUUUGUGGCUCUCAGAAACUCAAUCACUUCUUCUACGAUGUCAAGCCGCUCUUAGAAUUGGCCUGUAGUGACACAUUACUCAAUCAAUGGCUUCUUUCCAUUGUCACAGGCAGCAUAUCCAUGGGAGCUUUCUUUCUGACUCUUCUCUCCUGCUUCUAUGUAAUUGGCUUCCUUCUGUUUAAGAACAGGUCCUGCAGAAUACUCCACAAGGCUCUGUCCACUUGUGCCUCCCAUUUUAUGGUGGUAUGUCUUUUCUAUGGACCUGUGGGCUUCACAUAUAUUCGUCCUGCUUCAGCCACCUCCAUGAUUCAGGACCGGAUAAUGGCCAUCAUGUAUAGCGCCGUCACCCCUGUACUGAAUCCACUAAUCUACACCCUUAGGAACAAAGAAGUGAUGAUGGCUCUGAAGAAAAUCUUUGGUAGGAAGUUGUUUAAAGACUGGCAGCAACACCACUAGGACUAAUGAGGGAUAUCUGAUUUCUAUUAAGACUGAUUUCCAUCACUUCACUGUAAGAAAUGAUUUGUUUACCUGGUUUAUAUUUUUCUUUCAAAAAUUUUGAGCACAUAUUAUAUUAGGCAGUGUAGUAGGUUCAAGAAACACAGGAGCAAGCAAAACAAAUUCCAUAAUGUCAUCAAACAUAAAGUUUAAUGUGAUGGAGGCCCCAAAUAACCAAACGCGUAAGUACAUAUGUCAGGAUAAUUCGGUGGCAAGGAGAACUAAGGAGGUAGGAAGUAUGGGGAGGGUUAGAGUAGGAAUCUGCUGUGUAAAAAAGAAUGUGGCAUUUCUCCUAGGACAAAAACCUUUGGAAUUUUCCAAGUAAUAGAAGUAUCUUACUGAAAUUCCAUAUGAGAUAAUCUUUAUUUUUGCCUAUUUUUUUUCCUUUUGUGUUUCCUUCAGCAGGAAAGUACUGAUGAUAAUUUUUCUCACAACAGUUUUUAUCUAGAAUAUCAUUUUUGUUAAUCUUAAUUCUUGAAGAGAAUUUUUAAUGGGUAUUUAAUUUUAGGGAGAGAUUUUUCUAGCCAUUGAAAAUAUCUUGUUUUUCCCCAGCUUAUUGAAGUAUAAUUAACAAAUAAAAAUUGCAUAUAUUUAGGCUUCACAACAUGAUGCUUUAGUAUAUGUAUACAUUGUGAAGAGACUACCACAAUCAAGCUAAACCUACAUUACUGUCCCUGCAUUAGUUUACUGUUGAAUACUAGAAGUUCUUCAUUCUAUCUAACUGCAUUUUCAUACCCAUUAAGCCAAUGUGACAAGCUCUUUGUUUCAGUUGGAGUGUUUGCACAAUUUAAAUUUGAUAAAUUUUUGAUAGAAUUAAAUUUAAAUUUAUCCUCCAACUAAAUUUUUGAUAGAAUUAAAUUUAAAUUUGUCCUCCA